GGAAGCUGGUGCUGGACAGCUGGCGCCGGCAGCAGCGGACCGGCGGGAGACGGCGGCUUGGGAGCUGGCUGUGCUGCAGGAGCUGCGGCAGCCGCCGUCCUUGCACCUAAGGAACCUCUGCUGCCAGCCCUUCCUCACUUUUGGAAAUGGCGGGUGAAAUUACAGAGACCGGGGAACUCUACUCUUCCUACGUUGGGCUGGUGUACAUGUUUAACCUCAUCGUGGGCACGGGCGCACUCACCAUGCCCAAGGCAUUCGCCACUGCCGGGUGGCUUGUCAGCCUCGUCCUGCUGGUGUUCCUGGGCUUCAUGAGCUUCGUGACCACCACCUUUGUGAUAGAGGCCAUGGCUGCAGCCAACGCGCAGCUCCACUGGAAGAGGAUGGAGAACCUCAAGGAGGAGGAAGAUGACGACUCCUCCACAGCCUCAGACAGCGAUGUUCUCAUCCGGGACAACUACGAGCGGGCAGAGAAGCGGCCCAUCCUGUCUGUGCAGAGACGUGGAUCUCCCAACCCGUUUGAAAUCACAGACCGGGUGGAAAUGGGACAAAUGGCCUCCAUGUUCUUCAAUAAAGUGGGGGUCAACUUGUUCUAUUUCUGCAUCAUCGUUUACCUGUAUGGAGACCUCGCCAUCUAUGCUGCUGCCGUGCCCUUCUCCCUCAUGCAGGUGACCUGCAGCGCCACUGGCAAUGACUCCUGCGGUGUGGAAGCAGACACCAAAUACAAUGACACUGACCGGUGCUGGGGGCCCCUGCGCCGAGUGGACGCCUACCGCAUCUACUUGAAAGUCAUCUGGAAGCGAUUUCUUCUGUGUCUUCCCAGGAAUGCUCCUGAGACGCACACACACGGUGAGAAUCCUUGCUACAGUAACUGUCUCCAGGGCUGGCCUGUGUGUAGCAUCAUGAUUACUUACAAAAAGGGAGAUGCUUCUACCAGCAGCUCCCAGUGGCCUCCCAAAGCCCUUGACCUUCACCAGUGGAAAAUUCCAACCCCACUCCUUGUGCCUGACGACCCUUGUCCAUAUCCUGUGCUUCCCGGCGCGGCUGAUAUGAGUCACUUUCCCCCUUUCCUUCCCUGGAGGAGCCACAGAGCAGGGUGCUGGGGGGUGGAGGUCCCCUGAGUCACUUGCUGCUUCAGUGGGCUCUCUGGGGUGUCCCAGCAGGCCACUGCAGCUGGAGCCAGCGGUGACCUCAGCCCUGUUAUUAGGGCCCAUGGAGAUUAUCAUCAGGAUCUGCUAUCAGCUGACCUUGGAUUCUCAGGCCCCCCACCCACCCAUCCCUCCUGCUCUUUUGAAAAAUCAAAUGGGAAUGUGUGAGAUGCUCCAGCUCUUUCAAACGGGUAACCUUGCCUCCAGGCUAGGGAACAUCUCAGGAUUCUUUCUGCAGUUUCUCCGGCUUUGGUAGGCAACACAGUCAGAAGUUGGCAUUUCAUUCCUUCCUCUACAGCAUGAAGGAGCCAGGGACCCCUGGUGAGGUGAUAGGAUUGCGUAUGAACCAGUUCUGUUUGGGACUCAGACUGUCCCAAGUGUCUGGGAUGCAGGCGUGUGUCACUCUCCCCCUGGGAUCAAGGGCACUGCCCAGCACCUUUGUUGCACUUCCUUAUUCCUGCAUCACCUCCCAGCCAAUAUUCCUGUCCCCUGUCUGGACCCAUCCCUCCUCCUAGAGAGAGUCAGAGGGAAGCAGUGUCAGAGGGGACAGUGGGGACUCCCAAGUGCUGAAAGCCUCUGAAAGCCUCUCACCAUUAGGAAGAGCAAGCGGCAUCUACCGCUCACAGGUGGACAGAUGCUGCUGGGUCGCAGGUGGCCCGGCAGGCCCCGGCCGAACAGAGCCGGGAACGCAGAUGGCAGAGCGGAGCUUAUCCUGGCUGGAGACCCGGCCGCAAACUGCCCUGUUGAGCAGAGGGCCCUUCGUGGGCUGCCCUGGGACAGGACAAGGUCGCCCUGGCCUGCUCUCCUGCCUUGAACACAGGAGCUGUGAGAUCCACCUCCGGGGCACAGGUGACUCAGGAGAGGGAUACAGCCUGCAAGUGCCUGGCCAGUGCCCUGCCACCCCUUGUGACAGAGAGAGUCUUCCCAAGCUCCCUCCGGACACCCCCUUGAAGAAGUGGAGGGCCAGGGGGAUUUCUGUCUGCUGGCCUCUCUUCCUAGAGGGCCGGGUCAGUCUCAGAUUCAGGCUCAGGUUGACACCGGAAGGGUCAAGGGUCCUUCCAGCCCUGUUUGCGACAGCCCUGUUUUUUCUCGCUCUGCCAGGAUUCCAUCUUGGCCUCCCUCUCACAUGGCAACACUGGCCUUUGUCCAUUUGCAACACUUAAAAUGGUGUGCAGUCCCCAUUUCAAAACCAAAUGCUUUCCUCCUAAAAUAGUACCACUCAAGGAGAAAAUAUCCUUUUCAUGAGGGUGCAGAGGGAGUGAUGUGCCCACCUGGCAGUGCCAUGCGUGCUGUGAGUGCCCCGCCCUCCCACGGUUUACCUUGCAUCGGUGUAGCACAUACCAGUGACUUUUGACUCCCACCCACACAGUAAAGUACACAGCGUCAUCCCAUUUCACAGCAGGGAAAACUGACUGAGAGACGGGGGCUUCCUGGGAUCCCGGAGCUGAAGCAGACAGACAACAGCUCAGCUCUUUGGCCUCUCAGCUCUGUCCUGCCCUGGUGACACAGGCUUGCUCCACUUGCCCAAGACUCAGUUCCAUAGGCCCUGCCUUGGCGGUGGCCCCCACUGCCAUGUGCAGGCUGGGGCAUGGAGCACCUCUUCUCAGCCCUGGAAGCCUGACAUUUUCAAGUUGGUGGGGUGACCCGGCUGAGCAUGUUCCCUGGUGAGUGAGCGCCUUUGCACGUCUGCCCAUCAUUGUCACCGACUUGAUUGAUGCCCUGUCUGCCCUGGUGCCCCUCACUCCUAGAUAGCAAGGCCAGCUUUUCCUGGGCACUCAAGUAGUGUUAGAAUUAAGUGCCUCUUCCCAAGGACACUUCCUUCCCCUGCCAUGGUCUCUGUUCUUCUAGCGUCAGCCACUGUGCCCUGGGGCUGUGGCAUCUGUUAAUAAGUGGGUCAACGCUGCCUUCACUUGAAUAUUUAUUCUUGCCAGUGCUGGGGCAGGAGGUGGCUUAGAGGCCUUCAGGACCAGUGAGGAAGGAAAAUUAGUGAAGCAACAAGUUUGAGGAGCAGCAGUGACUUCACUGGACUUGGAGACUCUGGGGACACUGUGCCGCCUGCCUCCCAGGCACCACUCUUGUUGCUUUCAACGUCAGUGGUGCCCCCAGGGCACAACUCCAGUAGAACACAGUGAACACUGCCCCCGAGUUUAUGCAGCGUCCAGCCCGGGAUUGAGUGAAGUGCAGUCAAACAGGAAAGGUGGCCUGGGGAGGGCCUGGCAAGAAAGUGGACAGGAUAAGCAAGCUGUCUCUGUUUAGGAGUCUAGUGGGUUGGCCCGUCUAGAAACGGAAUGCAGGACCCUCAGCCCAGAAAGCAGACAGCCUGUCAAGAGUGUCCCUUCCUGGGCAACAUCCACCCUCUCAUGUGGUUCACGUGAGUUAGGACUCAGCCUCACACCAAACCAAGACGAGUCAGGAGGAGACUCCAGGACGCCUGGAGGGGGAAGGGUGUUGCUUCCAGGGUCGGGGACAUCCAAGUGCCUCCUUUAUAGGAUGGCGACCAUGUAGGGGCUCACUGGGGUGACCCGGGAAGCCCAUCUUCUCUCCUUUCCUUUUCUUCUCCCUCCCAACGCACCUCUUGUCAGUUCCUCCUCAUUCAGUUCUGGAGACUCUAGAAAGGUCGGGUUUGUUUUGCCUUUCACCUUUUCCUCCCCUCUCGCCUAUGGAGAGAUGUCCGUCACACCUGGUGGCACCGCAGGUGCACUGCGUGCAGUCGUUCUAACCCGUGCCCACCACCACCAGGAGCUGGACUCGGUGAGGCUUCGAGGUGUCUUCAGCCAGCUUUGGUGUGGGGUUGUGAGCCCCUGAGAUGCAUGUCCCGGGUGCUGUUUGUCCCACAUAUGCUGAGCCUUUGAGGUGUCUUCAGCCAGCUUUGGUGUGGGGUUGUGAGCCCCUGAGAUGCAUGUGCCAGGUCCUGUUUGUCCCACACAUGCUGAGCCUUCUGCAGUCAUCCCGUGAGACUGGGUGUCAAGGAAGAAUGUGUUUCUUCCCCGCACCCCAAAAAUGUGCGUGCCCGUACCCGCCACCCAAGCAGAGCUGGGAGUCUAACCUGGGUGAACUCUAACUUCAGACAGCGACUGCGCUCAGGCUGAAAUGGUGACCUCAAAGGAUUAGCUUGUCUCUUUCUUUUUCAAGGAAAUCAAUAAUACAGGGACAGGCCUGUGUUGUUCUUGCUUGCUUGCUUUUUUUCCCUAGGAGCUGUCUAUAUAUCUUAGACCAGGAAUGGCUUCUUGUCUUCCGUGUGCUUUCCAUCCCCCUACCCCAGCCCUCCCUAAAUGAAAUUCAGGUUGCCUGUCACUCACUCCCACACUGCAGCUUGUCUCUCUAGCUCCUAGCCAGGGACAGCGUGAACCCCCACCACCCCACCCAUUCCUCCGCCACUGCUGCUCCUGUCUGAGCACGGCCCCUGUCCCUCCUUUCUUCCCGGAGUUGCUCCAGCCUGUCCCUUCACCUUGCUGAGGACACCUGGGUGACGCCUCCCUGAGUCACCCUGUGACUGCCUCCUCCACCCUCAUCCCCAGUGCCCAUGCUUUCUCCUCCUGCUCAGGGAGAGGGUUGCUGUUUUUGUUUUUAAUGUCACUCUCAGGGACGUGGGUUCGGUUGACUGGCAUUAUGCCCACCAUCCAUCAUGCCCCACGACCUAUGACCUGUCCCCACCUUGGCCAAUACCUAUGCGCCAGUUGAGAGGAUGAUGCCUAGUCCCCCGUGCCACCGCCUCUAUGGUCUCAGUACAGGUGCCAGACUGGGGGACUCAGUGUCACAAAGCAGCAGGCAGUGGCUUCUUCUCCCUACCACUCCCUUACCCAGCUCGGAAGCUGCUCAUGGGCCUCUGUCAAGGUCCUGAGGGGUGACAGGGUCUUAUGUUCUUGCUUCUAAGCUGGUGACCGACAUAGCCCCCUUCACAGCAUGACAGUUGGGUGUCUCUGGCCCUGGUAGAAUGUGCAGGUUGGGUAUCCCUUCCCCAAAAUAUUUGGGACCAGAAGCGUUUCUGAUUUCAGAUUUUCUUCAGAUUUUUAGAAUAUCUGCAUUAUACUCACAGUAGAGCAUCUUAAAUUCAAAAAUCCAAAAUAUUCCAGUGAGCAUUUCCUUUGAGGAUCGUGUCAGUGCUCAAAAAGUUUCAGAUUUUGGAGCAUUUCAGGUGUUGGAAUUUUGGAUUUGGGGUGCUUAGCCUAAACCAUAUUUCUUUACCCCAUCUCCAUUGUCUGUAAAAUAAUGAGUAUAGCCUUGCAAAGACUUCCUACCCGCAGCAAGCCAGGUUUACUCCCGGGCACGUGGGGAAAACGGCAGUGUAACUUACCUGGUUGCUCAUCCCUCACCCCACCCCCAUUCACCAAUUCCCCCAGGAAGUGAAUGGAGAUGGGAAAUGAUCUGUUGCCAUGACCUUGACCCACACACACCCAGCAUUCUUAACUCCUAGGAACCCCAUUAUAUGAAAAUCCAAAGGUAUGAAAUAAAUUGGGAGGGUAGUUACUUGUUACAAAGUGAUUCCUUACUUUACAGAAGGAUUUGCUUCAGAUUUCUCUUAAGUACUCAGUUUCCCUAGUGUAUUUAAAUGUUGUUCUGUGAAAAUUAAGCAUUUGUAAAAGAACUUCAGGAGCCCUUCUCUUGUGUAAAGGGAGAUAUCCGUGUAUUCAUAGGCAAAGGUGCAGAACCCCAAAGCCCGGUUGAUGUUGCUGGAGAAACAGGCAGGCAGGGCUUGGGGUGGACAUCAUAGGCAGCCCACCUGAAAGCAGUAACCAGCGAUUCCCCUUCCCCUCUCCCCAUCCACAUCCCUGAGCUGGGAGAGCUCCGCGGAGCUUGAUAAGUAUAUACCCGAGCCCCACACCUGUGCACAGGCCAAUUUGGUUGGGAAGCUUCCAGGCAGGGCUCAGUGGGGGAGUAUCCAUCCCUGCUGGGGACCUUCUGCGCUGAGCUUUUUCAGGACCGUUUCUUUGCAGGUCUCAUCCUGAUCCCAGUCAGACCCCGAGCCCGAGGCCUAAGCCCUCCUUGUUUGUGAGUGGUGCAGUCAGGGAUAAAAACCCGGUGUGCCUCACUUCCCAAGCCACCUGGGCUGAUCCUGGCCACUGACCUGUGCGUGCACAUGCAUUUCCAGUCAUUCCCCUCGAGAAGCUGAGCCCCGGGCAGACUCCCAAAGCUCAACAGCCCAGUCCAUCCCACACUGUGCACCCCGCUGCUUCCAGAACUCCCAUUUCUGGGCAAAGAACUAAAAAUAGUUUUUAUUAUAUCUGUUAAGAGUACAUCCCAGUUGUUGAUUUCAGAUCUCUCCCUGCCACCUUUUUUAUUUUUUAUUUUUUUCUUCAUUUCACAAAAUAAAAGUGUCAAAAAACUCCAUAGUCUGUGGAAUCUAGCAACCUCCCAGUAGUUUGAGAGUAACAUGGAAUGUUCUUCAAUAUUUUGUGCUAACUAAAAUGAAAACUGUAUAUGCCAAA